ACUGGGCUCACUCUAUCGAGAGGUCGGAGGCUGCGAGUGUCGCUGCUGAAGGCUGUAGUGGACCGGGCUGGAUCGCGGAUUCUGAGCUACAUCGCGGGUUUGGGGGUGCAUCUUGGAUUUAGGGGUGGAUCGCUGGGUGGGGAGGGGGAUCUCGAAUUUGGAGCUGGGUGGGGGUGGAAAGGCCACGAGGAGCCGCGGCGUCUCAGGAGCGGGUGGUGGGCAUCUGAGAAGUCGCCACCAUGAGGAAGCUCCUCAGUUUUGGGAGACGCCUGGGCCAGGCGCUCCUGAGCUCCAUGGACCAAGAGUAUGCGGGUCGGGGGUACCACAUUCGGGACUGGGAACUGCGGAAGAUCCACAGGGCGGCCAUCAAGGGCGACGCCGCAGAGGUGGAGCACUGCCUGACGCGCAGGUUCCGGGACUUGGACGUCCGCGACAGAAAAGACAGGACUGUUCUACAUUUGGCCUGUGCCCAUGGCCGUGUGCAAGUGGUCACUCUCUUGCUGGACAGAAAAUGCCAGAUCAACAUCUGUGACAGACUAAACAGGACACCUUUAAUGAAGGCUGUACACUGCCAGGAAGAGGCUUGUGCCAUUAUUCUCCUGAAACGUGGCGCCAAUCCAAACAUUAAGGAUAUCUACGGCAACACUGCUCUCCAUUAUGCCGUGUAUAAUGAGGGGACUUCACUGGCAGAAAGACUGCUUUCCCACCAUGCAAAUAUUGAAGCACUAAACAAGGAGGGAAACACUCCACUUUUGUUUGCUAUAAAUUCCAGGAGACAGCAUAUGGUGGAAUUUUUAUUGAAGAACCAGGCAAAUAUACAUGCCGUUGACAAUUUCAAAAGAACAGCCCUCAUACUUGCAGUACAGCAUAACUUGUCAAGUAUCGUCACCCUCCUGCUUCAACAAAAUAUACAUAUCUCUUCUCAAGACAUGUUUGGCCAAACUGCCGAGGAUUAUGCUUUUUGUUGUGAUUUGAGAAGCAUCCAACAACAAAUUUUGGAACAUAAAAAUAAGAUGCUUAAAAAUCAUCUUCGAAAUGACAAUCAAGAAGCAGCAGCCAUGAAGAAUGAAAGUUUUAAAACACAAGGAGCAAGUUCAAAAGUCUCGCUCUAUCACCAGUCUGGAGUCCAGUGGCAUGAUCUCAGAUUACUGCAGCCUUCACCUCCCAGGUUCAAGCAAUUCUCCUGCCUCAGCCUCCCGAGGAGCUGGGACAACAGGCACAUGCGACCAUGCCCAGAAACAGCAGCUAUGAAGCCUGAAAAUUUGAAAAAAAGAAAAAAAAGAAAAAAAUUGAAAAAAAGAAAAGAAGGUGCAAAAGAACACAACUUAAAAGUGGCUUCAGAGGAAAAGCAAGAAAGGCUUGAAAGAAGUGAAAAUAAACAGCCGCAGGAUUCUCAAAGUUAUGGAAAAAAGAAGGAUGAGAUGUUUGGAAAUUUUAUGUUGAAGAGAGACAUUGCCAUGCUCAAAGAGGAAUUAUAUGCAAUAAAAAAUGACAGUCUCAGAAAGGAAAAGAAAUAUAUUCAGGAAAUUAAAAGUAUUACAGAAAUAAAUGCUAACUUUGAAAAGAGUGUAAGACUCAAUGAAGAAAUGAUAACAAAAAAAGUGGCCCAGUAUUCGCAACAGCUUAAUGAUCUGAAAGCUGAGAAUGCAAGGCUGAAUUCAAAAUUGGAGAAGGAAAAACACAACAAAGAAAGACUAGAAGCUGAAGUUGAAUCCCUCCAUUCUAACUUGGCCACUGCUAUAAAUGAGUACAAUGAAAUUUUGGAAAGAAAAGACCUAGAACUAGUUUUAUGGAGAGCAGAUGAUGUUUCUAGACAUGAAACAAUGGGUUCUAAUAUUUCUCAACUAACAGAUAAGAAUGAGUUGCUUACUGAACAGGUCCAUAAAGCUCGGGUGAAGUUCAAUACCUUAAAAGGUAAGCUCCGUGAGACAAGAGAUGCUCUCAGGGAAAAGACAUUGGCUUUAGAAAGUGUACAGCUGGACCUAAAGCAAGCGCAGCAUCGAAUAAAGGAAAUGAAGCAGAUGCAUCCAAAUGGGGAAGCUAAAGAAAGUCAAUCCAUUGGAAAGCAGAACUCUUCAGAGGAGAGAAUACGUCAACGAGAACUUGAAAAUCUCUUGCUUGAACGACAACUAGAGGAUGCUCGUAAGGAAGGUGAUAAUAAAGAGAUAGUCAUUAAUAUCCACAGAGACUGUCUUGAGAAUGGAAAGGAAGAUCUUCUAGAAGAAAGAAAUAAGGAAUUAAUGAAUGAAUAUAAUUAUUUAAAAGAAAAACUGCUUCAGUAUGAAAAAGAAAAAGCAGAAAGAGAAGUGAUUGUGAGAGAAUUUCAAGAAGAACUGGUCGAUCAUCUUAAAAAAUUUUCAAUGUCAGAGUCUCCACUGGAAGGUACAUCACAUUGUCAUAUUAAUUUGGAUGAGACAUGGACUUCAAAGAAGAAAUUAUUUCAAGUAGAAAUUCAACCUGAAGAAAAACAUGAAGAAUUCAGAAAAGUUUUUGAAUUAAUAUCAUUACUGAACUAUACUGCGGAUCAAAUAAGAAAGAAAAAUCGUGAAUUAGAAGAAGAGGCAACUGGAUAUAAGAAAUGCCUAGAAAUGACAAUAAAUAUGUUAAAUGCAUUUGCAAAUGAAGACUUCAGUUGCCAUGGAGACUUAAAUACAGACCAACUGAAAAUGGAUAUUCUGUUUAAGAAGCUAAAACAGAAGUUUGAUGAUCUUAUGGCCGAGAAGGAAGCUGUAUCUUCAAAAUGUGUCAAUUUGGCCAAAGACAAUGAAGUUCUUCAUCAGGAGUUAUUAUCUAUGGGAAAAGUACAAGAGAAAUGUGAAAAACUUGAGAAGGAUAAAAAGAUGUUGGAAGAAAAAGUAUUAAAUCUUAAGACACAUAUGGAAAAAGAUAUGGUAGAACUUGGUAAAGUACAAGAAUAUAAAUCGGAGCUGGAUGAAAGGGCAAUGCAGGCAAUAGAAAAAUUAGAAGAAAUCCAUUUACAGAAACAAGCAGAAUAUGAAAAACAAUUAGAGCAGUUAAACAAGGAUAAUACGGCUUCACUAAAAAAGAAGGAACUCACACUUAAAGAUGUGGAAUGUAAAUUCUCCAAAAUGAAAACAGCUUAUGAAGAUGUUACAACUGAAUUAGAAGAGUAUAAGGAAGCCUUUGCAGUAGCAUUGAAAGCUAACAGUUCCAUGUCAGAAAAAAUAACGAAAUCGGAUAAGAAAAUAGCUGUGAUCAGCACCAAGCUCUUUAUGGAGAAAGAGCGGAUGGAAUAUUUUCUCAGCACUCUUCCUAUGAGGCCAGACCCAGAGUUACCUUGUGUUGAAAAUCUUAAUAGUAUAGAACUCAACAGAAAAUAUAUUCCCAAAAUGGCCAUAAGAAUUCCUACUUCAAACCCACAGACUUCAAAUAACUGCAAGAACUCCUUGACUGAGAUGGAGCUGGACUGUGCAGAACAAAUAAUUACAGAAACAAAGAAAACUUUUGCUGCGUUGGGCCCUUGCUCCUAUCUACUUUCUUCUCUAGAAUCCACUGGUAAGCCACAUCUAAUGAAGAGAAUAUUUAACCAUAAAAUCUUAAGGAAAAGUUGUAUGAUUUAAAAGAUCAUAAAACUUUAUUACUGGGCUAUUUACAUGAAAUUUUAAUUGUUUCUCAUAAAAUAUAAAACAUCACAAUCUUUACUAAAGUAGAAUAUUUUCAUAUCAUAUGAUGUAUAUUUAUAUGUUAUUUUAAAUGAUUUUUUUAGCCUCCUUAAGUUUUAAGUGGAUCUUGCAAAUGAACACCAGUGUUAUUGAGUUUGACCUACUCAAAUUGCCUGAAUGUCAGCUGUUUAAACAGCCAAACAACCAAGUCAUCAUUGAUACUGUAGUAAAGGUCAUCUUUGCAUUUUACACUUUUUAUUACCAUAUAUAGUAGGAGACUUAAAGAGUAUCUGCCAGGUUUGUCCAUACUAGUGUUAUGAUUUUCUUUUUGUAGUUCAAUAGUAUUUUGUGUGGAGAUACUUUGAAGCUCUGUAAAUAUCUGGUUACUCCUCAAAACCCACUAGAUUUAGCAUUUCAUGGAUGACUUGUGUUUGAACAAGUAUUACUGUGAUGGUUGCCAGAUGAUUAUUUUUCUUAUUUUCUUCUUUGUUCUACAUGGAGAAAUAAAACCAAUAAAUAAAGGAGAAGGGAAAGUCA